CUCCCCUCUACUCUACCCAGCUUGCGCUCCCCAGCCGCAAGUCGGCCGCGCUUUGCCCGUCAGCGCUUGGAGCUUUCUGCGUCGCUUCCCGCUGCGCCUGCGCGGUCCCGCCUCGCCCCACGCGCGGGCUCGCGCUUCGGUUUCCCCAGACCUGCUCGCAGCACCCUGCUGUCUUCCCGGUCCGGCCCGCUGCCCGCGGCGCCAGCACCAUGCUCUUCUAUUCUUUUUUCAAGUCCCUUGUGGGCAAGGAUGUGGUCGUGGAACUAAAGAAUGACCUGAGCAUCUGUGGAACCCUCCAUUCUGUGGAUCAGUAUCUCAACAUCAAACUAACUGACAUCAGUGUCACAGACCCUGAGAAAUACCCUCACAUGUUAUCAGUGAAGAACUGCUUCAUUCGGGGCUCAGUGGUCCGAUACGUGCAGCUGCCAGCAGAUGAGGUCGACACACAGUUGCUACAGGAUGCGGCAAGGAAGGAAGCCCUGCAGCAGAAACAGUGAUGGCUCCUCCUCCUCUUCCCCUCCCUCUUUCAUUGGUGACCCAUAACCCCAAGUCCCAGCCCAGAACCCCUAACCCCCAAUACUUGAAGGGGUUUUGUUUUUUUACUAAUGAUGGUUUUGUGGGUUUUUUUUAAGGGAUGAGUGGAUGAGAGGAGUAAUAGGGAACAGCUAUCCUCUCUUGAGAAGGGGAGGAUAAGUAGGCUGGGAAACUUCAAAGCCUUCCCAGUCCCCAGCACCUGCCUUUCUCACUACUUCUCUGGAGAUGGUAGGAGAGUUUCCUAGGUCUUUCCAGGGCAGCAUGUGAUUCAUUUGGGGAUGGAAGGAAUCUGUCCCGCAUCGGGAAUAAAAUUUAUGAUGCAAA